AUGAACGGUCAAGGAGCCGUGGCUGCCGCGAGCGCCACUGCGUGUUGCCCAAAGCGGCACAGAAAACGCAACAUUCGGGGACCAGCCCGCUUCAGGGCCCCUACACCUUCCCUCGACCUGGAACCGCGGGACCUCGGAAACCCACGCUGCCCGCGCCGGGUUGGGCCGCCCCAGAGGCCGCAGCGCCCACGCCCCUCCCCCGCCUCCCCGCCCUCCAGCCCCGGCCGAAGCCACCUCGGAGUUGGCGGAGGGCGACCCGAGGCCACCUGCCCCUCUGGGGCCGAGGAUAAAGGGGGAAGGGCCCAGAGGCAUCCGAGGGACAGAGCGCCGGGCCGGGGUAGCCAGGCGCCCGCACCCUCCCGCCGGCCGGCCCGGCCCGAACUUUCUCGCUGCUCCGUGCCCGGCGCGCCUCUCCCUCCUCCAGACCGGCCGAGCGCCGCCGCUGCAGAGCGCGCCAAACUCCGACGGCCGCGGGGCCGACGCCACCUCUCGGACCCCCCCCCAGGACCGCCCCGAGGCCGCCGGGGGCCUCGCGCUCCGGGACAACCUCGCCGCGGCACGGGGCGCGGCACGGCCCCGCCGCGUCACUCACCUUCGGCCGCUCCUCCCAACCUGCCGGCCGCUCGCUCGCUCCGCCGCGGACCCGGAGCUCGGGGAAGGGCGGGGCGCAGGGGGCGGAGUCGGCCCCGGCUGGCAAGCGCCAGAAUUAAAGCCCGAACCGCACGGCCGCCGCCGGGGCGGGGAAGCCGGGGCGGACCAGCAAGCCUCUCACCCGCGGUGGGCGACAGCUGUGGCUGCGCCCCGGAGCGGCGCGUGAGAAGAACGGCGCGGGCCGGCGAAGCCCCGGCUGCUCCCUCCGCCCAGAGGACGCCCGGCUCCCCGCGGGGGCGCUCUUUGUACCGCGGAGCCGGCCGCGGGCGGCCCUCAGUGCGCCUGCGCGCCGCUGCAACUCCACCAGGCCCGCGGGGCACCUUCGUGCACCUUCGUCGCCGCGCCUGGCCCGCGGGCCUCGCCGCGGCGAGAACUAAGCAGAAGAACUUCCUCCACCGCGGUUCGCUCCUUCUGCCAACCCGUAUUUACCACGUCCAUCCUCGCACACACACCCGCAAGGGGAGAAGAAAUCCAGCCCCCGUGAGACGGUGCGGUGCUCCCAUCUCCGGCUGGGGCGGGGGUUCUGGCAACGAGGCUGGCCUGCUCGACGUCCUCCCCCAGCGCCUCUGUACCUCCUCUCCCUCCCCGGGUGAGGGGGACCGGAGCGUGCAGAGCUCUGUUUCCUGCAGGUGCCUCGUCAGCACGGUCGCCCCGGCGGCCAGAAACCUCCCGCCUCCAAGGGCACCUCCCUUGUGACCUCCGUGCAUUCGCCCUGGCUCGGCUGCAGGACAGAGUCCUCGGCGGAAAGGGGAGGAUGCGUGUUCAGAAGGUUGCAGGUCUCUGGGGACUCCACAGAAGACCCAACGCCUGCCUCGGGGGCUCAGGAUUGAACUGGCUUCCUAGUUCAGUCCCAAAUACUCGAUUUGGAGCAAUCCAGUAGGUCCAUGAGAAAUUAGUAGGGAUUGAGAAGCUGUGACUUCAGUCUUUUUCAAAUUGAAGGUGGCUUGAACAAACAGAAGAGGAGCUUGGGAACUGAAGGGACGACUUUAUAAAAACCAGAUUUUGUGAGGGCCUCAUCUGUGCAAGUCCAGGGUACUGAAGCUCCGUAGGAGGGAGAAAAUCAGGGUAUGGAAAAACUUCACUUGGCUCCUCUGUGAAAGAUUCUACAACAUUUUCUGUUGUUUCUGGCUUUCAGUUUAGGUCCCUCCUUUAAAUAUAAUUGAAUAAAGUAUCCUUUGCCUUUUCGUUUUCUGAUAAAUCACCUUCAUAUGUUAAAUUUCCUUCCACACUGCUGUUUCCAUAUUUCAGUUUCCAAUUUGGAGCAAACAAAGUUUCACUUGUUGUUUUCUGUAGUUGAACAUGAAUUAACAUGGGGCUCAUUUUCAUCCUUAAAAAAGUCUUCAUCAGCAUAGGGCCAGCAGAGACCUAAUGGCAUCUGCAGUCCAGGAUAAGAACCAACUUGCUCAUCAACUGAAGCACUUGUUAAUGAGUGGUUCAGAGUGAAGAGCCUUAUGGAGUUACCAGUUACAUUAAAGCCAGUUUCCAUUACAGAUUUUUUGAAAUUCCUAUUAUCUAUGGGAUCUCUUUCAGUAAGAGGAUAACUCCAUAGCUGACAUGUCACUUGUUUAUUAUUCUUGUUAAUUUUGCUUCAUGAGAGAUGUUUGACACGUGUAGGUUACUGCCACAGUUGUAACUAUUUUUUCUCCCCAUUUUGUUGUAGCUGCUUGAAGGAGUUAAAAAUAUGCUACUCUAGCAUGUUGACCAUUUUGAGUUAAAGGCGCUUAAAAAACAGCAGGUGCAAGAAGAUCACUCUACCCUUCCUUCUGUUUCUUAAAAGCAGCAGAUAAAAUUCCCAUGCAAAAGAUGUUCUCUCUCUACCAGAAGGAAAUAUUAUCAUCAUCAAGGAGGGGAAGAGUCUGAGGGAAAUAUUACAAACAAACUUGUUAGACUAAUCCUUAUCCUCUUCACCACUUCUUCACCAAUUAACUAGCAAGCCCCUUUUCCUUGUCACAUUUUCAUAAAGUACUUCUCUUUGUCUAAAUCAGUAUAUACAUGUUCAUCUCUAAUUGCAUCUUUGGGUCUUCAUUUCCUUGUAAAGUCUCCUAUGCCACACAAAACUUAUAUUAAACAAAUUCGUAUGCAUUUCUCCUAUUGAUCUAUGUCAAUGUAAUUCUCAGUUUUAACCAAAAGUCCCCAAAAGGGUACAGGUAAAAAAGUUUCCCCUUCGUGCUCCUCAGGGCUUUUCCUGUUUUUAAGGUGUCUCAGGCCCACAUGUCCUUUCCAGAGUCCUCUUCCCUGGCCCCUGCUUCAAGUACAAGGUAAAAGAUUUGCAGGAGCCCCCUCUGCAAGGAUGGCAGUUGGUAGCAGCCUUGUCGGCGGUGGAGGAUCUCCAAGGUCUGGGGGCUGGCAAUAGUGGAACUGUGGCAGCAGGAAUUGGGCCCAGGGAUGCCAGCUUCAUCUGGGGCUGUGGCUCCUGGGGCUUCUGUACAUCUUUCCUUUUUAUUGCUGGACAAUAUUCUAUUGUGUGGAUGUACCACAUUUUGUUUAUCCAUUCAUCCUUUGAUGGACACUGAGGUUGUUCCACUUUGGGCUAUUAUUAAUAAUGCUGCUAUGAAUAUUCAAGUGCAUGUUUUUGAAUAAACAUGUUUUCCU